GCUAGUCCCAGAGGCCCAGAGUGGCUCGCCUGGAGUCUCUGUGGCGCGGUUUCCUGUACCUGCCUUGGGAUCCGGAGGGAGGAAGCUGGGACACCCGGGAGUCAGGAAAUGAAAAAAUGACAUCACAGGUCAGAACCUUACAUCGACUUGGUGAGUGGUUGCUGGUGAGAAUUAAGACCCUGGAGGAGGGAGCAUUUCCACACUGAGAAGGGGACAGUAGGGACUCGGUGGCUUUUGAGGAUGUAGAUGUGAACUUCACCCAGGAGGAGUGGGCUUUGCUAGAUCCUUCCCAGAAGAAUCUCUACAGAGAUGUGAUGUGGGAAACCAUGAGGAAUCUGGCCUCUAUAGGGAAAAAAUGGAAGGACCAGAACAUUAAAGAUCACUACAAACACCGAGGGAGAAAUCUAAGAAGUCAUAUGUUAGAAAGACUCUAUCAAACUAAGGAUGGUAGUCAGCGUGGAGGAAUUUUUAGCCAGUUUGCAAAUCAGAAUCUGAGCAAGAAAAUCCCUGGAGUGAAACUCUGUGAAAGCAUUGUAUAUGGAGAAGUCAGCAUGGGUCAGUCAUCCCUUAAUAGACACAUCAAAGAUCACAGUGGACAUGAACCAAAGGAAUAUCAGGAAUAUGGAGAGAAGCCAGAUACACGUAACCAGUGUUGGAAACCCUUCAGUUCUCACCACUCCUUUCGAACACAUGAGAUAAUUCACACUGGAGAGAAACUCUAUGAUUGUAAGGAAUGUGGAAAAACCUUCUUUUCUCUCAAAAGAAUUAGAAGACACAUCAUCACACACAGUGGAUAUACACCAUAUAAAUGUAAGGUGUGUGGGAAAGCUUUUGAUUAUCCCAGUAGAUUUCGAACACAUGAAAGAAGUCACACUGGAGAGAAACCCUAUGAAUGUCAGGAAUGUGGAAAAGCCUUCACUUGUAUCACAAGUGUUCGAAGACACAUGAUAAAGCACACUGGAGAUGGACCUUAUAAAUGUAAGGUAUGUGGGAAACCCUUUCAUUCUCUGAGUUCAUUUCAAGUGCAUGAAAGAAUUCACACUGGAGAAAAACCCUUUAAAUGUAAGCAAUGUGGUAAAGCCUUCAGUUGUUCCCCAACCUUACGAAUACAUGAAAGAACCCAUACUGGAGAGAAACCUUAUGAAUGCAAGCAGUGUGGGAAGGCCUUCAGUUAUCUCCCCUCCCUUCGACUACAUGAAAGAAUUCACACUGGUGAGAAACCCUUCGUAUGUAAACAAUGUGGUAAAGCCUUUAGAUCUGCCAGUACCUUUCAAAUACAUGAAAGGACUCACACUGGAGAAAAACCUUAUGAAUGUAAGGAAUGUGGGGAAGCAUUCAGUUGUAUCCCAAGUAUGCGAAGACACAUGAUAAAACAUACUGGAGAAGGACCUUAUAAAUGUAAGGUAUGUGGGAAACCCUUUCAUUCUCUGAGUCCAUUUCGAAUACAUGAAAGAACUCACACUGGAGAGAAACCUUAUGUAUGUAAACAUUGUGGUAAAGCUUUCGUUUCUUCAACAUCAAUUCGAAUACAUGAAAGAACUCAUACUGGAGAGAAACCCUAUGAGUGUAAGCAAUGUGGGAAAGCCUUCAGUUAUCUCAACUCCUUUCGAACACAUGAAAUGAUUCACACUGGUGAGAAACCCUUUGAAUGUAAGCGAUGUGGUAAAGCCUUUAGAUCUUCUAGUUCCUUUCGACUACAUGAAAGGACUCACACUGGACAGAAACCCUAUCAUUGCAAGGAAUGUGGGAAAGCCUAUUCUUGCCGUGCCAGCUUUCAGAGACACAUGUUAACACAUGCUGAAGAUGGACCACCUUAUAAAUGCAUGUGGGAAAGCCUUUAAUGCUCUGGGUUCAUGUCAGAUACAUUAAAAUACUCACUGAAGAGAAGCCCUAUGAAUGUAAGUAACGUGGGAAAGCAUGAAAUUCUGUCAGUGCCUUUUUUAAUACAUGAAAGAAUUCUAGAGAGAAGCCAUAUACAUGUAAGUAACAUGGGAAAGCUUUCAAUCAUUUUAGUUCCUUUCAAAUACAUGAAAGAACUCAUCAUGGAGAAAACCAAACAAAUGCUUUUUGGAAAGGAACCCAUAUUUGAGAGAAACCCUGGGUAAAGGGUGUAGGAAAGGUUUUGUCAUCACACAACCCUGUCACACAUGAAUGUGUAGUGGAGAGAACCUUGGUAAAUGUAAAGAGUGUGGGAGAGCCUUUAGUCAUUUUAGUUCCACUUGAAGCCAUGAAAGAACACACAAAAGAGAAAGCUCUUGAAUAUAAGCAAUGUCCACACGUUUUUAGCCAGCCCACAUGCUUUCAACAACAUGUAAGAAUGUACCCUGGAUCAAAACACUAUAAAUGUGAAAACUACAAGGAAGGUUUUCCAUUAUACUUUUAAAGUCAUUUGAGGGCUCUGGCUCUGUGGCUUUGUGGGUUAAAGUACUUGUCUGGCAAACAGGAGAUGCUGGAUUUCAAUCCCAGCAGGGCCUCACUAGUUGAGGUAUUGAAUUUGAACAGAUGUUUUGGCUCUGGCUGGGUGUGGUGGCUCACACCUGUAAUCCCAGCACUUUGGGAGGCUGAGGCAGGAGGAUCACUUGAGGUCAGGAGUUUGAGACCAGUGUGCAAAACAUAGCAAGACCUCAUCUCAGAAAAAAAAAAAAAGUCAUUUGAAAACUUCUAAUACAGCAAAAUCCUAUAAAUGUAAGUACUUCAAAAAGCCUCAUGCAUAGCGGGUCAUGUAGUCUCUAGAAAAUACAUAACCUGAUGGAAAUGUAGAAGCUAUAUGUAUAUUUUGUUAAUUAGUGGCUCAUAUUUAAAAUAGUUCUCUGACUAUGGAUUUCAAAUGCUUAAUCUCACAAAGAAAUGUUAAAUUGAUAUAAUCCUGUAAGUAAUCUGAAAGCAAUAGUGCAUGAAUUUCAUAGGUAGUGUUGUUUUAGGUCAGUAAAUAAAAUAUUUGUCUUUCCAUUUUGAAAUGUGUUUAAUCCAACAAUGAAUUUAAAUGUGUUUCUCAUAUUCAGGUAUGUUAAAUUGUAUAUGGUUGCUUAAUUGUUCUGUGAUUGAGGACCACUGAAAAAUAAGUCUUAAUAAAUGUUGGUAUGAACCUACUUGCUUCAUUUAGCAGGUUCUUGAUUCCCUUUCCACAUUAUAUACAUUCCAUCAUAUUUAUUGGAACAGCUCCUUUUUUUUCCUUUUUUCUUUUUUCUUUCUUCUUUUUUCUUUUUGAGACAGGGUCUCGCUCUGUGCUCUGUUGCCCAAGCUGGAGUACAGUGGCAUGAUCUCGGCUCAUUGCAACCUCUGCCUUCUGGGUUCAAGUGAUUCUCCCACCUUAGCCUCCUAGGAAGCUGGGACUACAGGCAUGUGCCACCACACCUGGCUAAUUUUUUGUAUUUCUAGUAGAGAUGGGGUUUCACCAUGUUGGCCAGGCUGGUAGAACUCCUGACCUCAAGUGAUCCACCCACCUCAGCCUCCUAAAGUCUGGGAUUACACGUGUGAGCCAUCACACCUAGCCCAUUUUUUUUUUCUUGGCUCAAAUAAUUUUAUUUUGCUUCCUAUUAAAGAGUUGUUGUUAAUUCUAAGUAUGUAAAGUUUAUCACAGACUGUAGUCUCGUGAAUUAUUAUUUUAACCUGUUGUUCUUUACUCCUUGUUAUUUAUUCUGGCUGCUCUUUGUAUAAUUGAUUUUGGGAUAAGGAGACAGCUAUGAUAGAAUAAUAAAAUCUAAAAUGGGA